GGAUUACAGGCAUGAGCCACUGUGCCUGGCCUUCAGUUUUCUUAUUUGUUGGAAUCAACUUAGUUAACAAAUACUUAUCAAGUUCUCACUGUGUGCUGGGCUGUAUGUCAGGCAUUGAGUAUAUAGCUGUAAAUAAGACAGGCAUGGCUCCUACCGUCAUGGAAAUUACAGUCUAGCAGGAUCAAGUUAAAUGAAAUAAUAUAAUGUCAAAGUUCUUUCACAAAGUUGGUAUUCAAUAAAUGCUAAUCCCCUUCCACUUCCCUUCAAAUAUACGAUCAUUAUAUAUUCUGACACUCAAACAUAAGAUGGCCACAGACAAUUUCAUACAUACAAGAAUUGUGUUGGGAGCCCAGACACCCAUAGUAUAAGGGAACUCUUCAGCAUUAUGUCUCACGAAACUUAGAUCAGUGUGUGGUCUUGAUUUAAAUCCAUGUAACCAAGGGUUUCUAUUUAUGGUCAACAAUGAAUCCUUAUUUUUGGUGGACUUUAAGGAAUUAUACAAAUAUUGCCUCAUUGAUGCUUUCAGACCAUUUGUGAAGUGAAUGAGAAUAGGUAUUAUUAUUAUUAAACCCAUUUUACAGAUGAGGAAGCGGAUGGAAGCACAUUCUUCGGGGCCUUCUUUGUUCUCUAGUCCUAGUCUGCACAAAGGAAGCACUGGAUAGACGCUGUGUGCACAUUGACCGUUCUGGCAACUUGGAAAGGAGAGGUACCCCGCGUUAGCAAAAACAGAUAUUGACUCAGGGUUGCAUUGCGGCCGCUCAGCUCUUGCCUUCUCCCUCAUUUCUUCAGGUGGGUGAGAAAUGGGCGACUGGAGUUUCCUGGGGAACAUCUUGGAGGAGGUGAAUGAGCACUCCACCGUCAUCGGCAGAGUCUGGCUCACCGUGCUUUUCAUCUUCCGGAUCCUCAUCCUUGGCACGGCCGCAGAGUUCGUGUGGGGGGAUGAGCAAUCCGACUUCGUGUGCAACACCCAGCAGCCUGGCUGCGAGAACGUCUGCUACGACGAGGCCUUUCCCAUCUCCCACAUUCGCCUCUGGGUGCUGCAGAUCAUCUUCGUCUCCACCCCGUCCCUGAUGUACGUGGGGCACGCGGUGCACUACGUCCGCAUGGAGGAGAAGCGCAAAAGCCGCGAGGCGGAGGAGCUGGGCCAGCAGGCGGGGACUAACGGCGGCCCGGACCAGGGCAGCGUCAAGAAGAGCAGCGGCAGCAAAGGCACUAAGAAGUUCCGGCUGGAGGGGACCCUGCUGAGGACCUACAUCUGCCACAUCAUCUUCAAGACCCUCUUUGAAGUGGGCUUCAUCGUGGGCCACUACUUCCUGUACGGGUUCCGGAUCCUGCCUCUGUACCGCUGCAGCCGGUGGCCCUGCCCCAAUGUGGUGGACUGCUUCGUGUCCCGGCCCACGGAGAAAACCAUCUUCAUCCUGUUCAUGUUGUCUGUGGCCUCUGUGUCCCUAUUCCUCAACGUGAUGGAGUUGGGCCACCUGGGCCUGAAGGGGAUCCGGUCUGCCUUGAAGAGGCCUGUAGAGCAGCCCCUGGGGGAGAUUCCUGAGAAAUCCCUCCACUCCAUUGCUGUCUCCUCCAUCCAGAAAGCCAAGGGCUAUCAGCUCCUAGAAGAAGAGAAAAUCGUUUCCCACUAUUUCCCCUUGACCGAGGUUGGGAUGGUGGAGACCAGCCCACUGCCUGCCAAGCCUUUCAAUCAGUUCGAGGAGAAGAUCAGCACAGGACCCCUGGGGGACUUGUCCCGGGGCUACCAAGAGACACUGCCUUCCUACGCUCAGGUGGGGGCACAAGAAGUGGAGGGCGAGGGGCCGCCUGCAGAGGAGGGAGCCGAACCCGAGGUGGGAGAGAAGAAGGAGGAAGCAGAGAGGCUGACCACGGAGGAGCAGGAGAAGGUGGCCGUGCCAGAGGGGGAGAAAGUAGAGACCCCCGGAGUGGAUAAGGAGGGUGAAAAAGAAGAGCCGCAGUCGGAGAAGGUGUCAAAGCAAGGGCUGCCAGCUGAGAAGACACCUUCACUCUGUCCAGAGCUGACAACAGAUGAUGCCAGACCCCUGAGCAGGCUAAGCAAAGCCAGCAGCCGAGCCAGGUAACCCAAAGUGACAAACCUUCAGUGGAGGGAUGUUGAAUAGAAGAGGUAUGUUUAUCUUGGAGGCACGUGAUUUUCUGGCUACUGCUUAAUCUUACCCCUAGCAAGCAACGUUAUUCUACACAGACUUUCUCCUAUAUGGUGAGAGAAUUAACACAAUCCGAGGCCUGAGAACCAGAGAGUGCAUCCUUGACUCUAAUGGCUGCACUAUUGCUCCCAUAGUUUUGUUCCUGAAGAUGCAUUUUAGGAAGAGCCUUAUGAAUAGCUUGAUCAUUACCAGAAUAAAGUGUCUAUCUCAACUAGAGCCUAAUACAAAAAAGAAAAAGAAAAACGAUAUCCUGUUCUAAAUAAAACUGCUGUUUGGUACCAGUUGUAGAAAUGAGGGCUACUGGUCUCCUUAUCUCAGGUGGGACAUAAGUGUGUGAUAGAGCGUCUUUCCUCAGAUGAGGCAGUAUCCUGCUUCAAUGAACGUACCCACACUGUCCCCACAUUUUCCCUCUUAGUCUUCCCAAUAAAAGGAGAAGCCUAUUUAGGAAGAAACAGACACAGGCAUCAAGGGGCUGCAUUUUUUUUCUAUUUCUGCCAUUUAGUAGCUGUAUCAUUAUUGUGCCUUGAGCUCUCUUUACUUCAGUUUUCUGUCUACAAACUAAAGCUGGCAUUUGCCACCUACCUACAUCCAGGGGUGUCCUAAAGAUUGAGUUGGCUGCCAAGCAUGAGGCCUGCUGAGUGGUACCAUUCCCUGAGAGAUUCCUCCAACAGCAGUAAGACUGGGAAGAAGGGCAGGUGGAUGGUUUCCAUCUGUCCCUCCAACCUGCCUCGUAGUUACCUGGUGAGUUUUUCAACGUGAAAUAGACACUCCAGAGAUCACUUUUCUCAGAAGAGAUUCAAAACAGAAUUUAACCCCAUAUGUUUAGUAGGAACCUGAGGCUCAUUGACCUUAAUAAAUGACUGGAGACAGAUUGCCAAUUACUUUCAUUCUCUGAGAAAGAGGUCCCAUCUUAAGCGGCCACACAAACACAGCCAGUUUCCAUUUAGAAGCAGCUGCAUGUCUGUGGUGGUCUUUACUCUAGGCAGCUACACCACUCAGCAUCUGUUUUGAGGCAAAUAAUUAUGACUGAGUCAGGAUUAUAAUCCCCAUGGGCUUCAUUAUGUCCAGAUUUCAUUUCUACUCCUAGUCGGUCCCUUGUUAGAUAAAAACCCUAGGGCACAUGGACCUACCAAUAAAAAGAUGCAUUAGACAGCGGGACAUCAGUAGUACAGCUCCCUCCAGAGGAAAAGGGCUAAUCACUUGAUAGCAGUUCUAACACCACCCUCAGGGGAUAUCUGUGACCAAGAAUAGAUGUACUCAAAGUUCAGUGAGAAAGUUUUGAGCCUGGCUGUGUAAACCCUGGCCUAGUGUUUUGGGCAUUAUUUAAAAAAAAAAAAAAAAAAAAGAAAGAAAAGAAAGAAAAAAGCCUGUCUGCUUUUCACCAUGUCUUUGUCCCCUGCCACACAGGGAAGCAUCCAGUACAGCACUGGACAGAUAUUCCUGAAGGUCUGUGUGACCUGGGGACCCACAAAGAACACUGACAUUCAAGUCAGGGGUGUUGAUUGCCCCUCCUGACUCUGGGUAUUCCAAGAUGCCACUUACCUGCUCUAUGAGACAAUUUUCUCUAUGUUAGUUGAGGAUGAUAAGUUCUGCCCCUCCUUCACAAGAUGUUAUAGGUCUUUUUUAAAGCUCACUAAUUUGGAAAUAAAUGGAAAAGAAAGAAGCCAUCAUCAAAUUUUGUAAGACCAUAUUGUAAAAUGUAUACUGAAGCAGUGACAGUCAUCACUUUCAAAUACUGCAUAGAUUGUUAACUAAGAUACUGAUAAAAAGUGAGCCAAUAACUAAAGUAAGGGAAAUAAAUUUGGAGGGGCAGCAGGUAGUCUUGAAUUCCUAAGAAUUAUGGUACAAAAAAAAGAAUGUCUUUAAUCACGCAAGAAUUGGUUGCUGAAAGAGGUGCUAAAGGUACUCGGCUUAGUAGAGCUCACAUAUGGAGAAGCGUCAACCCCUGAGAUAAUCUCUGACUCAUGGCAGAAGGGGCUCCAUGGAUACGGAAAGAGCUGCAUGCAGGAACUCUUCAGUCCAGGCCAUGUGGAAGGCCUAGGACAAGAUUGGUACAAACCACUGCUCCUCUCCAGUUCCCGAGAAGGGUCAUUAGGCGUGCUCUAAGUAAGAAUGAGAACACCACCCCAACUGCAUGUCCCAUUCCAUUCCCCCAGCCUCCUCUUCUCUCCUUUCCCUGACCAUGAUUUACCCUCUAUGCAUACUGUGUGCAAAUGAUUGCCCAACCCAGCUUAGCAAAGUUUAGAUGAGAAAGGUUUGCCUGGUUGGAAGAAAAACUCUUCUGAGUGUAAAUACAAUCUGUAAAACUACUAAGUGUGUACCUAGAAGUGAUAGCGAAAUAGGCAAGGAGACUUUCCCCUUUUGCAAUUAUUGUAUUAUAACUAAAUAUGUACUUGGGGAAGGGAGGAGAAAAAGGAAAAAAAAUUCUCGGUUCAGCAUUUGGGUAAGAGGAAAGAAAAACUUUUAUGAAAGACAGUUCACUCUCCACUGCCCUAGACAUUGCAGCUCCCAGAGCCAGGAAAAAGUGGUAUUCAGCUCUGGGAACCGAAUACCACAUAAAAAAGUAGCCACCAAGUUGCAGUGGGACAUCCCAUAGUCUCCAACGCCACUGCUUUCUGGAAGUUCUACAGAGCAGACAAAGAAGAUUCUAAAAGAAUUCAUAAGGUUGUCUGAAGGGAAAAGUAGAUGACCCCAUGGCCUUUUUCUGCAAUUUUUUCAUCUAUAAAACAAAGUGGUAAAGACUCAGUUUGUUAUGAAGCACAUUCAUAACAAACUUCCUGGGGAAAUCUCUGGCAAAAGAGAGACACGUUAUUGGGAUGGUGGUCCUGUAUUCUCCAACCUUCCACAUCCUUGUGCCAGAGCUAAUAGUCGUGUGUUAGACUGUUACAAAGCAAAUAAAAUUAACUUGACUUUUCA